GGGUCAGUGUCACCUCCAGGAUACAGACAGCCCCCCUUCAGCCCAGCCCAGCCAGGUCUCCUACACCGCCACCAUGCCAUUCGGUAACACCCACAACAAGUUCAAGCUGAAUUACAAGCCUGAGGAGGAGUACCCCGACCUCAGCAAACAUAACAACCACAUGGCCAAGGUACUGACCCUUGAACUCUACAAGAAGCUGCGGGACAAGGAGACUCCAUCUGGCUUCACUGUAGACGAUGUCAUCCAGACAGGAGUGGACAACCCAGGUCACCCCUUCAUCAUGACCGUGGGCUGCGUGGCUGGUGAUGAGGAGUCCUACGAAGUUUUCAAGGAACUCUUUGACCCCAUCAUCUCGGAUCGCCACGGGGGCUACAAACCCACUGACAAGCACAAGACUGACCUCAACCAUGAAAACCUCAAGGGUGGAGACGACCUGGACCCUAACUACGUGCUCAGCAGCCGCGUCCGCACUGGCCGCAGCAUCAAGGGCUACACGUUGCCCCCACACUGCUCCCGUGGCGAGCGCCGGGCGGUGGAGAAGCUCUCUGUGGAAGCUCUCAACAGCCUGACGGGCGAGUUCAAAGGGAAGUACUACCCUCUGAAGAGCAUGACGGAGAAGGAGCAGCAGCAGCUCAUCGAUGACCACUUCCUGUUCGACAAGCCCGUGUCCCCGCUGCUGCUGGCCUCAGGCAUGGCCCGCGACUGGCCCGACGCCCGUGGCAUCUGGCACAAUGACAACAAGAGCUUCCUGGUGUGGGUGAACGAGGAGGAUCACCUCCGGGUCAUCUCCAUGGAGAAGGGGGGCAACAUGAAGGAGGUUUUCCGCCGCUUCUGCGUAGGGCUGCAGAAGAUUGAGGAGAUCUUUAAGAAAGCUGGCCACCCCUUCAUGUGGAACCAGCACCUGGGCUACGUGCUCACCUGCCCAUCCAACCUGGGCACUGGGCUGCGUGGAGGCGUGCAUGUGAAGCUGGCGCACCUGAGCAAGCACCCCAAGUUCGAGGAGAUCCUCACCCGCCUGCGUCUGCAGAAGAGGGGUACAGGUGGCGUGGACACAGCUGCCGUGGGCUCAGUAUUUGACGUGUCCAACGCUGAUCGGCUGGGCUCGUCCGAAGUAGAACAGGUGCAGCUGGUGGUGGAUGGUGUGAAGCUCAUGGUGGAAAUGGAGAAGAAGUUGGAGAAAGGCCAGUCCAUUGACGACAUGAUCCCCGCCCAGAAGUAGGCGCCUGCCCACCUGCCACCGACUGCUGGAACCCAGCCAGUGGGAGGGCCUGGCCCACCAGAGUCCUGCUCCCUCACUCCUCGCCCCGCCCCCUGUCCCAGAGUCCCACCUGGGGGCUCUCUCCACCCUUCUCAGAGUUCCAGUUUCAACCAGAGUUCCAACCAAUGGGCUCCAUCCUCUGGAUUCUGGCCAAUGAAAUAUCUCCCUGGCAGGGUCCUCUUCUUUUCCCAGAGCUCCACCCCAACCAGGAGCUCUAGUUAAUGGAGAGCUCCCAGCACACUCGGAGCUUGUGCUUUGUCUCCACGCAAAGCGAUAAAUAAAAGCAUUGGUGGCCUUA